ACGUCUGUGACCCCUGGGGAAAUUAUUUAGCUUGUCUUUGCCUUGUUUUGGUCUGUAAAAUGGCGAUCUUAUAGCCUAUUUCAGAAUUGUGAGGAUUAUAUGAGAAAAUACACGUUAAACGCUUAGAACAGCGCCAGGUGCUGCUCAGUACAUAUUAGCUCUGCUUUUGCUCUCCACGUUUUAGGAGUUCAGAAUGACUGUGACCUUAUUUUCUCAGAGAAUCAGGACACUUGGUCUCACACGUGAGAGUGAAGUUAUGAAGACAGUGAUAUGUAAUAUUUGACACUCAGACGAUCCUGGACGUAGUAUUACUGUACACGUGGAUAAAUUAGCAUUUCUCCAAGAGGCUAAUAGAAAUGUUAAGUUAUUUCGGUAGAAAGAAAUGUGUGUGUAUAUAUAUGUAUAUACAUAUGUGUGUAUAUAAGUAUAUGUAUGUGUAUAUAUGUAUGUAUGUAUUUGGAAGGAGAGGACCUGGGGUCUUAGUAUAUGUGAAGGGCAGACUCUGGAAGAGGAAUUAAAUUCGCCCUGCAAAGAUUUACUUGAAGGACAAAACUUGGGGAAUUUCUGGUGAAUGUUUCAAAGAGGCUGAAUUUGCCUAUGAGAAACAGUUCGUGAGAGUACUUUGCAAGAAUGGAAUGCUCUUCAUUGUGCUAUGGAAAGUUUCUUAUCUCAGGAUAUUCGGGACGUUGGAGCGAAGUAUGCCUAAGUCUAGGGCUGCACUUUUCACUAGCAGUUUCUGCCUUGAUGGAGAUGUUCCAUAAUCUGUGCCUUUAGGCACUAGUGGUAGCCUAGGCACAGUGGCUCUUCAGCACUUGAAAUGUGAUAAGUGUCACUGAGGAACUUAAUUUUUAAUUUUAUUCAUAAAUUAAUAAAUUGAUUUACGUUUAAAUACCCACAUGUGGCUAGUGGUAGCUACUGCAUUGGACAGCACAGGGCUACAAUUUAGAUUUUGAGAGUCCUUCCGAGUCUUGAUAUGGUUGAGUUUUAAAUCAGAUAAGCCAGCUCUUUGGAACAUUUAUUGCCAUAGGGAAUUGUAAUUAUAUUCAAAUAAUGCCUUUCAUUCAAAUACUGCAGUUCAGACCAUGGGUCUGUUAGUACUUAUUUACAUCUUGACAAAUUAAAGCAAAACGUUGUCUCCUAGGUUGUACAGCUAAUGCCAGAUUCAGAGAGCUAUGACAGUAUUAACUGGAGUUUUCUUUAAACAUUAUUGUACUAUUUUGUGAUUGUCGGUUUCUGCUAUCUUUUACCACUUUGGUUGGUUUUUCAGUGAGAAGUUUCCAGCUCUUAUUCAAGUUUUUUUCUUUUUUAACCUUUUGUGUAAUAAAGCGAUUUGAAAAAUUGUAACUCUUGAGCAUUAGGACAUUUUAGAACUAGUUUUAUGGUUAUCCAAAUCUUUUGGAGAGAUAAGUGAAAUUAGGUAAUAGAUGUUUCACAAAAUUACUUUACUUGAAAUAUGUGCAUCUGUUUUUUUUUUUUAAAGCAAGUGUAUAUAAAGUCAAAUUUGAAAAUAAAACUAAAAGAACAAAUAAAAAACCUUUAUAGGUAGCGGUAGCACCCUUAACCUUGGCCUGAUGUCUGUAAAAUGGUGCCCUUGGGCCAGGCACGUUGGCUCAUGCUUGUAAUCCCAGCACUUUGGGAGGCUGAGGCCAGAGGAUCUCUUGAACCUAGGAGUUCAAGGCUGCAGUGAAUCAUGGUCAGGCCAGGCUUCCAGCCUGGGCUGCAGAGGGAGACCUUGUCUCUUUAAAAAAAAAAAUGAUGCUCUUGGUCUUAAGGCUGAAGAUAAUUGUUAGAUCUGGAGCAAUAACUUAAAGCUCACGAGUUAAAUCAGAUGGAGAGAAUAGCUCAUAAUAUACAAAUCAGAAUGGGGUGCUUUUAUGGGUGACUAUAGUAUCUUAAUUUUUCUGAGACAGUCGUAGUAUAAAGCCUGAUUGUUCCAGCACAAUUAUUUUAUUUAAUAGAACCCCUUUCACUAUCAAAAUGUUCGAAUUGGGACCACAUCAUAAUGUCACCCUACUGUUAGCCUUGUUGGGACUUGUAAUAUAUAGUUUUAGGAUGAUUAACCACAUUGCAAUAUCAGAAAUACUUUAUUAUUUUUGAGAUGGAGUUUCACUCUUGUUGCCCAGAUUGGAGUACAAUGGUGCGAUCUCAGCUCACUGCAACCUCCCCCUCCUGGGUUCAAGCGAUUCUCCUGCCUCAGCCUCCCGAGUAGCUGGGAUUACAGGCACAUGCCAGCAUGCCUGGCUAAUUUUUGUAUUUUUUGUAGAGACAGAGUUUCACUAUGUUGGCCAGGCUGGUUUUGAACUCUUGAUCUCAAGUGCUCCACCCGCCUCAGCCUCCCAAAGUUCUGGGAUUACAGGUGUGAGCCACCGUGCCCGGCCAGAAAUAUACUUUAAAACAGUGACAAAAUUACUGUUUUUGUGUCUAAAUAAUAAAUAAGAUACCUGGAAUAAGGCCAGCAAGUGACUUUCCCAUUUAAGCCACUGAUAAUUUUAAAAUUUUGCUUUGAAUAUAAACCUUUAGCAGCUUGAGUUUUGGUUCCCUCUGGAAGAAAAUCAUCUUUUGGUGGGGGUGACUGCAUGGUAGUCUAUGUCAGUCAAAUCAGGUGAUUGAGUAUUUGUGUUGAAAUAACACUGAUUUUAUUUUAUGGUGAGGUUGAAUAGUGAAAUCCGUCAGAAAUCUGAUUAUGUAUUAGAAUGUUAAAGAAGGGUUUUGCUUACAGUUUACUUAAUGAAAAAUAAUUCAGCCAUAUGCAUUAUUAUAUUAAGUUUAUACUGAAGUGGGUAAAAUAUUUUAUUGAGGCUCUAACACUUGAUUUGAGUUCUCGCUCUGCUGCUUCCUAACCAUGUGAUUUGGGACAAAUUAUUUAAUCUUCCUAAGAAUACUGGGUUCCUCAUUUAUAAAAUGAAGAUGGUAAUGGCAUCUGCUUCUAGGUUCAUAAGAGGUUAAUUUAAAUAACUCAUGUGAUGGGUUGUGUGCAGUUCAGUAACUGUUAGCUGCUGUAGCCUUAAGUUUAUUGGAUAAUCUAGAAGUGAUAAUAAUGUUCUGAGAUGUUAUGUGGGUUGGUGAACAGAGCACUAAGACCCAAUUCUGUAAACCUAGCUUUUGCCCUUUUCUGGCACAUUCUUUUGUCAUUUCAGUUAAGGUAUUUAACUUAUUAAUAUCAGAGCCUCAAUUUCCUUAUCAGUAAAAUGGAAUUAGUACCCAUCCUCAUCCCGCUUUCUCAUAGGACUGUUGGUGGCAUCAAAUGAGAAUUACAUUUAAAAAUUAUCGUCUUACUUUACAAACAUUUUUAUAUUGAAUUGGUUUUGUCUCAUCUUGUCUACCUUCAGCCUCCACUAAAGAGUGACCUGCAAAAAUUGUUGUGUAAAUUUUGUGUAACAGCAUGGAUAGUGUAUAAUAGGCACUAUUACUGAAGACAGUUCUCUUUUACAAAUAAUAUUGUAAGUCACAGGCUGGGUGUGGUGGCUCACACCUGUAAUCCCAGCACUUUGGGAGGCUGAGAUGGGUGGAUCACUUGAUGUCAGGAGUUGGAGACCAGACUGGCCAACAUGGCGAAACCCCGUCUCUACUAAAAUUACAAAAAAAUUAGCCGGGCAUGGUGGUGCAUGCCUGUAGUCCCAGGUACUCAGGAGGCUGAGGCAGGAGAAUCGCUUGAACCCGGGAGGCGGAGGUUGCAGUGAGCCGAGAUCGUGCACUGCACUCCAGCCUGGGCGACAGAGCAAUACUCUGUCUCAAAAACCACACACACACACACACAAAUAAUAUUUUAAGUCACAGUAAUGGUGCUUUUUUGAUCUGGUCACAAUAUAUUUUCUACGGAAAACAACCCCAUACUACUGCUAAGGGAGAACCAACAUUUUCUUGGGCACUUGAUGUGUUCCUUCCGUUGUAUCUCAUUUAUCCAAACAUAUUCCCACCUAAUAGGUUAUACUAAUGAGGCUCUUACUUUCUAGAAUUGGUCUGUGAGGCUUUUUUGUACUGUAGUUCUCCCUCUGAAAAUACCUGGCCCAUAGUUAAUGGGUAGUGAAGGUUAAAUAAGAUAAUGAACAUGAAAAUCGUGGCCGGCUCUGUGACUUCAUGCCUGUAAUACCAGCACUUUGGGAGGCCAAGACAGGCCCGGGUUGCUUGAGCCUAAGAGUGAUGGGCAAUAUAGUGAGACCUGGUCUCUAGAAAAAAUUUAAAACAAAAAUUAGCUGGGCCGGGUGCGGUGACUCACAACUGUAAUCCCAGCACUUUGGGAGGCCGAGGCAGGUGGAUCGCCUGAGGUCAGGAGUUUGAGACCAGCCUGGCCAACAUGGUGAAACUCUGUCUACUAAAAAUACAAAAAUUAGCCGCGUGUCUUGGCGUGCACCUGCUACUUGGGAGGCUGAGACAUCAGAAUCGCUUGAACCCUGGAGGCGGAGGUUGCAGUGAGCCAAGAUUGUGCCAUUACACUACAGCCUGGGUGACAGAGCAAAACUCCAUCUCAAAAAAAAAUGUAGCUGAGCUUGGUGGUUUGUGCCUGUAGUACCAACUGCUUGGGAGGCUGAGGUGGGAGGAUUGCUUGAGCCCAGGAGGUGGAGAUUGCACUGAGCUGAGAUUGUGCCACUGUACUCCAUCCUGAGCAACAGAGAGAGACCCUGUCUCAAAAAGAAAAUAGUACUCUGUUUGGUGUAUGGUAUGUAGGAGUUACUGAAAAGAUGCUGUUGAAUUCACAGGACAGUAAAUUGAAACAAUUUAUGUGAAUAUACUUUAUAAACUAAAAUAACAUACAAAUAUAAAUCAUUAAAAAAUCUUGAAAUGUACUUUUGCUGAUUUAAAUGCUAUAGUGGUUUUAUGACUGAAUUCUGUAUAUUUCACUUUAUUCAUAUUAGUCUUUAAAGGUCUACUCUUAGUCAUAACAUUCUUUGAGAAUAUACAUGUUUAACAGUAAUCUUUUGUGAUAUAUUUUCAAGAAGCUAUGCUUUUGCAUGAGUUAAUCAUCAUCAUCAGCAUGAACUAAAUGCCUUAUAUGUACAAGGCGGUUUACUAAGGGCUUUACGUAUGUUAUUUUAUGUAACCUAUAAGAGAAGUAAUUUUAAUCUCCAUUUUAGAGAUGAGGGAACUGAGGCAGUGAGGUGGCAUAACUUGCCCAAGGUCAUGUGUAAGUGUUAGAGCCUAUAAUUUAACUCCAGAGCCUAGCUCUUUACUGCUUCCAUUGUGGUUUGGCAUAGUCAGAUAUUAAUAUUUCACAACACAGUUCACUGUGACAUACACAUUGUGGAGGCCUUUUGGGUUAGUUAUGAUAAACUUUUAUUUGUAUAUUCUUUGAUGUAUAGUAGAAAGAACUCUGGACCAGGUGUCGGGGGACCUCAGUUUUAGUCCCAGCUUGUAUCACUAAAUAGUAGUGUGUCCUUGGGCAGUUCAAGAAACCCCUCUGGACUUCAGUUCCUCACCUGAAAAAUGAGGGAUUUGGAGGAAAUUAGUGAUUUUCAAACUGUAGUUCUGAAGUCUGCUCAGAUGUCUUUGGUUCCCUCCCACCAAUUUGCAUAUAUGUUUGUCUGUUAUAGUUGCUUAUCCAUCUACCUAAGAUUUUCUUUUAAACAAAGAAUUUCUUAACUGAGUGUUUAAAGUCAUCAGUCUCCAAGAUAACUUAAUGACCAUGUAAGUCCCCUGACUGCUAUGUUUACAACUUUUCAGUUAAUUUCACAAUAUUUUAGUGUUUUAGGAGAUAGAGAUCUUUUACUAAUGAAAAAACUAAAGCACUAAAAUGAGAGGAUUGUUAUUAAAACAUAGUAUAUCUAAAUGGCCUGAAUAUUUCAGGUUAUCUGCUAUCUGGGAUCAAAGCCUGUUGUUUAUUGGAUUUGUGACCUUCAGCCAGUCUUAGUUUCCUCAUUGGUAGAGGGAGAAUACUUGUCUUGUAGGGUAAUUGUGAAAAAAAAAAAAAAAAGUGAGCUAAUACUGGUGAAGUACCCUUUAUAAACUCCAAAUUCCUCUAUUUUUUACAUGCCUACAGUAAAUCCCCCAGUCCUUUUUCUUUUUGGUCACAUAAACUGUUUUUAAACACAUCAGAUAUUUUGUAAAUUGUUUAUGUUUAAUGCAGAAUUCUCAUAAGCUUUAAUAUUUCUGAAAUGUGACUCUAGACUGGAAGAGAGUUUUGAUUUUUAAGGGAGCUGCUUAUUUUUUUGACAUGUUUGUCAAAUACACUUACCUCUUACUGUUAGGAGUAUAAUUGCUGCCAAAAUCUUCCACAUAUCUCAAAAGUUAACCAUUAAGUAACUCUUUAAUUAAGUUUGUGUAAGAACAACAGUGUUUUAAUGUUGGAAAAGUAAGUGUGCUAUGUGCCAUUUGUCAGGGCUUAAGGAUAAUCUGAUAGGCACAUUUGCAGUGCACCUUAGGGACUGUUUUUGCAAAGAAAUUUUUUUUUUAAACUCAAUUUUUCUGUGAGAGUACUGGAUAUGAAAGCAUAUGGAAUAGAAACUUAAUGUGAGACUAAAGAAGGAGGAUAUGCUAGAAACUCCUGUGUCUCGGAGCAGUCUAUCACUGGGCUCCUAUGUCUGUUCAAAAAGAUGCUCAGGUAGGAUAUGUAAUGCUGCACAGUUUUAGCUGUUUAUCAUCCAGAGAGAAAGGAUGGGGGUAGUUUUCAUGUUUACAGGGUGUUUUGAUAUUUUCAAUUCAGAUUUUUUUUAGUGCCCAUUAUAUGGAUUCCUGUGAGAUAAAUUAUUCCUGACAGAGAAACUGAACUUAUGAGAUUAGUUGAUCCUUAUAUCCUUAUACAAAGUUCUAUUAUAUUGAUUAAUUAUCCUUAACAAAAAUCUUGUGACCAUGGCUUUUAUUUCAGUUUUCUGCUUUACAACAUCUCUCACAAAGCUUCUGCAGCUUUUUAAAAUCUCCACUUGAAUGUCUAAUAGUUGUCUCAAACUUAACAUAGGCCCAACUGAACUGUUUUUUUUUUCCUUCCCAGUCUUCUGGAUCUCAGUAAAUGGCACCACCAUUCAACCAGUUUCUAAGGCUCCAGAAUUCGGUCAUCCUUGACUGCGCUUCUCUCACACCCCACGUGUAAUCCAUCAGCAAAUCAGUUCUGCUUUCAAAAUGUAUUCCAGAAAUCUGACCACUUCUCAUCAUCUCCGCUUGUUAAACUAAUUCAACCCACUGUCAUCUCUUGUCUGCACAACCUCAAUAACUUCCUAACUGGUCUUCUUGAUUGCACUCUUGCUUCCAUAUAGUAUAUUCUCCCAGCUGCUGGAGUUAUCUUUUUAAACCUAAAACAUUUCAAGUAACUUCCCUUUUCAAAAUUCUCUAAUAGCUUCACAUUACACUCAAGUGAAAUGUAAACUCCUGUGGCCUAAAGGCUUUAUAAGAUCUGCCCUCUUGCUACCCCUGUGUUCAUAUCUUUCUAGCCACACUGGCCACAGGAUUUUGGUACUUUGCUGUUCUUUCUGUUGGGAAGUUCUCCAGAGCUCCCUCCCAGAUCUUAUAUUAAAUGCCACCUCCCAGUUGAAAUCAACUUGUUUUUUUGAUUUCAUAGUAUUUGUUAUUUCCUCAAAUUAUAUUUGUUUAUGUGCUUGUCUCUUGCAUUAUAAUGUAUUUCUUUUUGUCUGACUUAGUCACUACUAUAUCCCUACCUCUUAGAACGGUGUUUGGCCUGUAGUAGGUGCCCCGUAAAUACUUAGAUAUGAAGAAUCCAAAGCACUGGUGGUGUUGGCUUUAAAUAAGAGUGUGUCUUUAUUAUAAGAGGAGGGAAUUAAGGGAGGAUACGAUACACUGUCUUUGGUGGAGGAGAGUGGAGGGAAUGACUAAAUGAUAGCUUUUUAUUUCUCUGGAAGUAGAAGAUGAUGUCAACUGUCCAUAGCUAGGGGAGGGAUUCACUGUGGGACAGAGGCUCAUUCAACAAAAAUAAUUAGUAUGCACUAAAGUAAUUUAAUAUUAAACUAAUAUAAACUAAAAUAAUUAGAUGUCAGAGAAAGAAUUUCUUUUGUUUACAUAUCUGGGAAGGUUUCUUGGAGAUGGGCUUAGGUCAGUAGAGUUUGGGUAGGUUGAGAGAUACUGUAUUGUUUCAAAAGGUAUUGCAAGUAGAGAGAACUGUAGGGGUAAAGGUUCAAAAGAACAUGGAAUGGUUCUGGAGAUAGUGAAAGUUUGAUUUGACUGUGGUAGAAAAGGAGGCUGGGGAGGUCAGGUGUGACUGAUUUGAGAUAAGUUUAUAAACCAGGCUUUUUAAUACCUUCCAAAGUCCACUUAAAAUGGGGCAUAUAUUAAUAUAUUGAGAUUACCUUUGUGUUAUUCUAAACACUAGGUCUAGAAGUUUUUAUAGAUAUUUUAUGUAUUUAAUUUUUAAUUUUUUUCAUUCUCAGUGAUUGACCAUUUGGUAUUAUUUUUCACAUCAGAAGAAAUUUAGAUCAUGAUGUAACCUGAUUAUUUUUUUAAACAACAAAACGAAAACUCAGUGCAUAAUAGUGUUGGCUUAACCAUAAUUGUUUCCUGCCUUUGGAAUUUUAUGAAAAUAAAAAUGUUCUAAUUAUAAAAGUUUUCUAUUAAUUUAUAUUAUGUGAGAUGUUCAGGUUAUCAUUAGAAUUGAGACUCUGUAGAUGCUCAAAAUCAGUACAUAGGUCUGCUGAAAUAGUUUUCUUCAGCAAUAUAGAAGAAAAGAUUAAAACUUCUCUCUUUUAGUGGAUUGACUGAUAGUUUUCACAGUCCAGAUUUUGAUGAUGUUUGGAGGGUGCAGAAACUAGUAAUAAGGUUCUCAACAAUUUGAGGUCUUUUAAGCUUAAAGAUGUUUCAUGGUAUUUCUUCUGUGGUCAUUUAGUCCCCCAAAAUAUGAGAUCUAACUAGAAACCCAGUAGCAUGUUCAGUGCAUUUUGUUUAACUCACUUUUUGUGAUUAACUUCACUACAAUUAAAACUUUUUUUUUGAUAGCAAUAUUUUCUGAGGAAAGGCGUGCAUCCUUAAAUUCCUUCAUUUUAAAUUGAAAGGUAAAUGCCAAUUUUUCUUCUCUGGAACACAGUUUUACAGGUGUGUUAUAAUAUUAGCUAUUAGCUUAAUGAUCAGGUUUAAAUACUAUUAAUCAGAUAUGAACUUAUUCCUUGGGUUCACAUUUAAACUCUGGCAUGUUGAAAUAAUCUAGGUCCCAAUCUGCACAUCUGAAUUCAUUUUGUAAAAUAUGGCAAACAGAUGCAUUUUCAAUUGAAAGCUGAAACAACUGCAGGACAUUAACCCAUUGAAAAGAUUACAGUAGGUUUUCAGUUCCACAGUAACUGUAUUUAUUAGUGAAAAUUGACUUGAGUGCUUCUGCUUUUAACAGACUUUUCUUUUUUAAUGUCUAGAAGAAAGGAAAUAGAGCAUUGGAAUGAUAGGACUUUGAUGUGUAAAGAAGUUAAUGUCAAAAGAAGUUAAUUAUCUAAAUCAAACAAUGUGGGUAUGGGAAAUAAUUAUUUUAAAGAGUCUAAUGACCUAUCAGCUCAUCAUGUCAAGAAAAAUGUUAUUCACCUGUUUGAUAUAAAAAUUGACUUGACUGUGAAAGGAUGAUCAUGGUUAUAAUAAACUAGGUUUGGUGACUGGAUUUGAAAAUGAAAAAGGAGCAGAUUGCUCCAGCAGUGUCUCAGGACAUUUGACCAUAGGAUAAUCCCAUGGAAUGGCAUGUCUGUCAAAUCAGACAAGUCAACUCAAAUCAUAACUUUCUGGAGGCUGGGGUUACUACUUACUCUUUGAGUUUAACAUGUUCUCGAAGAUAGCUCUGUCAGCCUUCUAUUGAGACAAGGGAACAUUUCCUGAGGUCUUUGAGAAAUCCAGGCUCCUUUUUUUCGCAUUUUGUCCCAAUUCUGCAGGACUAUUUAGGGAAGUCCUUUGUUUCCUGUUUUCCCCCAGUCUUGGACUUGUGAUUUUUUUUUUUAAUCCGAGUCUCAAAUGGUUAUGUUUCUUUUCCUGUGUUAUUUGUAGAGAAAAGUACUUAUUCCAAAAGUCUUUUUAAACAAUGGCACAAAUUUAGGCUUAAAAAAAGCGAUGGUCUUUCUUAGCAUUAUGUUCUUCAUAUGUUUUAGAAUUUUGGUUUUCGGGCUCAGUUUAAGUGGAACGUUUUUGUUUUCCUUCGCUUUUUGUGCUCUUGCCUUCUUGGUAUAGUGGUUUUGGCCUGGCUGUUAGGGCCCUCAGACUAGACCAGAGGGAUAUUGGGAUAUUCCAAACCUAGUCACCUAGCUAGUGUGCUGCUUGCCUUAGAUCUGUGUCCUGUCGCCUUCUCAAAAGCUUCAAAUAAAGCCUAUCUCCAUCAGUGAUUUGUAGUAGCUUUUUUUCCCCAACCUUCUUUCGUGGGGCCCAGCCCUUCCAUCUCAGCCCUUGAUGAAUAAUACGGCAGCUAGUCCAAUGUCUACUGCAACUUCAAGUAGUGGAAGGAGUACAGGGAAGUCUAUAAGCUUUGCAACAGAAUUACAGAGUAUGAUGUAUUCUUUAGGUGAUGCUAGAAGGCCUCUUCAUGAAACAGCAGUUUUGGUAGAAGAUGUGGUACACACUCAGUUAAUUAAUCUGUUACAGCAAGCUGCUGAAGUUUCUCAGCUGCGGGGAGCAAGGGUAAUCACUCCUGAAGAUCUUCUGUUUUUGAUGCGCAAAGAUAAGAAAAAACUUAGAAGACUGCUAAAAUACAUGUUUAUCCGAGACUACAAAUCAAAGAUUGUCAAAGGCAUCGAUGAGGAUGAUCUUCUCGAAGACAAAUUGAGUGGCAGCAAUAAUGCGAACAAAAGACAAAAGAUUGCUCAGGACUUCCUCAACUCUAUUGACCAGACAGGAGAACUUUUAGCAAUGUUUGAAGAUGACGAAAUUGAUGAAGUUAAACAAGAAAGAAUGGAGAGAGCAGAAAGACAAACUCGAAUUAUGGAUUCAGCUCAAUAUGCAGAAUUCUGUGAAAGUCGACAAUUAAGUUUCUCCAAAAAAGCUUCCAAAUUUCGAGACUGGUUGGACUGCAGCAGUAUGGAGAUAAAACCCAAUGUUGUCGCAAUGGAAAUCUUAGCAUAUUUAGCGUAUGAAACUGUGGCACAGUUAGUGGAUCUGGCUCUUCUUGUGAGGCAAGACAUGGUAACCAAGGCAGGGGACCCCUUCAGCCAUGCCAUUUCUGCAACCUUCAUUCAGUAUCACAACUCUGCUGAGAGCACUGCAGCCUGUGGUGUUGAGGCUCACAGCGAUGCCAUCCAGCCCUGCCACAUCAGAGAGGCCAUUCGACGCUACAGCCACAGGAUUGGCCCACUUUCCCCAUUCACAGAAACUGCUGCUGAAUUCCAUGAAGUUCUGUGGAUUGUGCUGCCAUGACUUCGUAGACAGACACUGCUUAAAAUGCCUACCGCAGGAAUGGGAUGGCUUUUCUAGCCUGCUGAUGUGACAACUGUGAUGUGCCUGCAACAACAGGAAAGGCAAUGUUAUAUUAAGGUGAUUUCUUGUGAACAAAAUAAAAUACAAAUUUACCUUUCUUUUAUCUGAGGGAGUGGGCUGGUCUGUUGUGACUUUCAACUUGCUGACUCCUCCUCUUUUCCAGCCCCUCAACCAUCGGUCUUGUUUACUAGAUGGGCUGUUCAGCUAAUUAAUGGCAGGAUGUUUAGGAUAGUCUGUAGGUGGACAAGAAUGCAGAUCACACAGUUUUGAAAUUUUAAUUUGAGUAGAUUUACUGCCCUCAGCUCACAUACCUUAAAAGCAGUGGUUGCCCCCGUCCAGCGUUUUGUCUGCAUUUUAUUUGAUAUAUUUUAUAAUCCAGGUUUGGAACAAGGAAACAAAAUUAAAAGGACAGUGAGUUUUCGCCUUCCCUUACACCACCAACUUUACUUUCCAACAUUUGUUGACAUGUGUUUUAGUGACAGCUAUCCAUUUUAUAAACUUACAGUAAUCAAAGAUCUAACAGACCUGAUAAAUCACCUGUUCCCACCUCCUUUCCCCUUCACUCCACUUAUAGUAUGUGUCAUUUUCAAUGCCUGCUUCCCAACUUCCUGCCAUCUGCCUUUCAUGUGUGUUUUUCCUCACACAGAACCUCUUCCUCCAUCUUCAUUUCCCUCCUUUUCCUGUUCCUCCAAUCCCCAGAUCCACCACUCCUGCACAUGCCAUACACAUUUAGAAGCCAAGUAUUCAGAAUCAGUAGAAGGGGAGCAGAGUGAUUUCUUGCUUCCUCCCUUCAAAGCACUACCACACCUAGACUGGAAAUGUGGGCUGGGUAAUUUCUUGCUGUUAGCAGCCGAGCUACCCUUCUGGCAUCUAUACUUUCUCCAGUAAAUGAGGAACCGUAACUCUUUGGAACAAACCAAAAUAUAGCAGAUGUAAUUGUACAGUUCCUGAUUAAACUUCAGUUGCAAAAAAGAAAGUUAUUUCUUUAAUUCUGUGGGAGUUUUGUAUAAUUUUACUUUUAUGGUUUUUACACAUACUUGAAACACUCUUUCUAAAGAAUUAAUAAAAACAGAAAUGAGAAACAUGAAAGAUCUUUUUCUUGAUACUGCUCCUUUUUCUUGAUACUGCUCAAGAGAGCAAGCCUCUCUUGAUACUGCUUCCUAGAUUUAAGGGUAAAGAAAGUAGAAAUAGUUCUCCCUUCACCCAAAUUUGGAAGUAUAAAACUUUCUGAACAUGCCAUUUAGAGGUUAUGUCAUUAGCUUUCCUGCCUUCUUAUAUUGUAAUAGUUGCGAUUCAAAAACACUGUUUCAAUUUUAAAUUCAAGACUUUUUAUUUGAAAACCAUCAGACUCAAAGAAUUAUGAGGCUCAGUUAAUAUUAUUAUGCCACAUUAUUUACAUUUGUUAACUGUCAUUUACCUGCUCUAUGUUAAUCUUUUUAGAAAAAAUUUGCAUUUCAGAAACAAAAAGCACGGAUAGAUAUAUAAUAUCAAAAUAUUCCCAAAGGAUUUUGAUGUUCCAUCUAUGCUUGUUAAAAUGUAUGAUUAUGAUUAAACUUUUUAUCAUUCUUAUUUUCCUUGGCAUCCAUAAUCAUGGAAAAUUACAAGCUUGCAGUAAACAUCCUAACUUAACUUAACUUUUAAACGAUAGCAUUUAUUGUAUUUGGUUUUGAUCUGCCAGGCUUAUAGAUGGUAUAAAAUUUUCAGGGGAUAAUUUUUCACAUCAAAAUUCCUUCUCUCCCACAUUAUACAUUUUAAAGUAUGCACAAGGCAGAAAAUAUAGGGUUUGGGUUUUUUUCCUUCGUUUUAUUCCACCUGAUCUCCUUAUAGUCCCAGAGAAGGAAGACUCAAUGUACAUUUCUCUCAGAAAUAUGACAGGUCUGUGUUUUUGUUGGUCUGGCAUAUGUUUGUCUAUCUUGAACAGUCUGACAGGUAAUUAUUUAUAAAAUCUGGUUUUGCCCAGUAAGUUCAUAUAAAACCUUUCAUUUUUCAUCAUAAGCCAGUAAGCUGAAUUUAGAAUAAAGCAAGGUCAUUUAUGUCUGUCCUGAACCAGCCUACAUGUCCCCAUAAUUGCUCAAUAUUUUUAAUUCCCUUUUCUAUUUUUUAUACUUAGGUUCUUUCUCUGACUCUUUGCACAAUACUAAAUUUGAAGUGAAAUAAAACUUCCUUCAGCAGUGACUAUAGAAACAAAAGAAAAUUUACAGAAGGAAUGUUUAAGAAAACUUCAGUAAAUUAUUUUCUCAAUAAUCAUAAUGUUAGAGCAGAAGAUAGUCUUAGAGAUCAUUAAGAACAGCUGCUCAUCUUGCAAAUGAAAAAACCAUGGCCUAGAGAGGGAAAGUGAGUUUCCUAAGAUCACUCAAUAAUGUAGUGACAGACCAGAGAUGAGAAUCGAUGGUCCCUAAUUUUCAGUCGGUAUUAUACAGUAUUUUCUACCAUACUGGGUUAGCAUAAGAAUAUUACUAAGACAUGUUGGGGUUUUAUGGCAUAUUUAUCCUAGACAACGAUGUAAAUUUAUUUAAAAACUGUACUAAUUAUGGAUACAUCCUAAAGCAUACGUGUUAUAUAGUAAAAUCUUCAGUGUGACUGUGGUAUUAAGUAAACAGUCUGUUAUCUUACACAUCAGGCUUAACUCUAAGUCAAAUGGAAAUAUACAAAGCUAGUUUCUAUUUUUUGUCCCUUGUAUUUUAGAGACUGAAUUUGAAAAUAAAUAAGCCAAUAAAUAAAUAGCGUCUCUUGAUACUGCUUCCUAGAUUUAAGGGUAAAGAAAGUAGAAAUAUUUCUCCCUUCACCUAAAUUUGGAAGUAUAACUUUCUGAACGUGCCAUUUAGAGGGUUAUGCCAUUAGCUUUCCUGCCUUCUUAGAUUGUAAUCGUUGUGAUUCAAAAAUACUGUUUCAAUUUUAAAACCAAGACUUUUUAUUUGAAAACCAUCAGAAGCACAAAUAUUUUUUAAAUGGUGUAUAUAAUUCCUGUAUCUGGGGAGAACCCUUCAUUUAUUGCUGUUCUUUGUUUUUAUAAAAUAAUAAACAAGCCAUGUCUGAUGCUUUUACCAUGUAGAAGACAAAUAAACAUAACUGGUGAUUCUUGGUCUGAAAGAAAA